AUCAUUUUUCUUCUCCGGCCCCAUGGAGGAAGUGAGAAAGUUGGCACAGUCACGCCGGGCUUCGCAGGACCAGGUCACUCAGUGACAGAUGGACAAUGCAAGAAUGAACUCCUUCCUGGAAUACCCCAUACUUAGCAGUGGCGACUCGGGGACCUGCUCAGCCCGAGCCUACCCCUCGGACCAUAGGAUUACAACUUUCCAGUCGUGCGCGGUCAGCGCCAACAGUUGCGGCGGCGACGACCGCUUCCUAGUGGGCAGGGGGGUGCAGAUCGGUUCGCCCCACCACCACCACCACCACCACCAUCGCCACCCCCAGCCGGCUACCUACCAGACUUCCGGGAACCUGGGGGUGUCCUACUCCCACUCAAGUUGUGGUCCAAGCUAUGGCUCACAGAACUUCAGUGCGCCUUACAGCCCCUACGCGUUAAAUCAGGAAGCAGACGUAAGUGGUGGGUACCCCCAGUGCGCUCCCGCUGUUUACUCUGGAAAUCUCUCAUCUCCCAUGGUCCAGCAUCACCACCACCACCAGGGUUAUGCUGGGGGCGCGGUGGGCUCGCCUCAAUACAUUCACCACUCAUAUGGACAGGAGCACCAGAGCCUGGCCCUGGCUACGUAUAAUAACUCCUUGUCCCCUCUCCACGCCAGCCACCAAGAAGCCUGUCGCUCCCCCGCAUCGGAGACAUCUUCUCCAGCGCAGACUUUUGACUGGAUGAAAGUCAAAAGAAACCCUCCCAAAACAGGGAAAGUUGGAGAGUACGGCUACCUGGGUCAACCCAACGCGGUGCGCACCAACUUCACUACCAAGCAGCUCACGGAACUGGAGAAGGAGUUCCACUUCAACAAGUACCUGACGCGCGCCCGCAGGGUGGAGAUCGCUGCAUCCCUGCAGCUCAACGAGACCCAAGUGAAGAUCUGGUUCCAGAACCGCCGAAUGAAGCAAAAGAAACGUGAGAAGGAGGGUCUCUUGCCCAUCUCUCCGGCCACCCCGCCAGGAAACGACGAGAAGGCCGAGGAAUCCUCAGAGAAGUCCAGCUCUUCGCCCUGCGUUCCUUCCCCGGGGUCUUCUACCUCAGACACUCUGACUACCUCCCACUGAGGCGGCUCCAGCCCCAGACAACAGCCCAGGCAUCUCCUUGGGCUGGGACUUCUUACCCAAAGCACAUGCUUAGCUUAUCUUUCUUUCCAUUUACAGUCUCUUUCUUCCUUUCUAAUCCUAUCUGGGGAGCUCCUGGCCAGGAUAAUAUAUUUGCAGAUAAUUCUGGACCAGAGACUUGGUGCGGGGUUAACACCUUCAUCCAGAUUGGGUGCCAGCAUACAUUUUCUGGUGGGCCUUAACAUCCCUCCUGCUUUUAGGAGAAUUCACAGAACCUACUGUUCCUUUCAGAUGACCUUUUGGAAAAUAGUUCCCUUUGCCAACAGAAACAUGCCAGAAGGAAUCUUCUCAUCUUUUAUCUAACUAUAUGUACAGCUCUCCCCUCCCUUGUCCUUGAAAGUAGGAUAUAGCGAAAGGCGAGUCCAGGAGCUCAGGAAGAAGAGAUGCACUAUAUGUUUACACAAUUAAUUCAUCCCUUAAUUUAAGUCAUUUUCAUGUGUGUGAGUUUGCUGGUUGUAAAUACUUUGUCCUAAGAGAUUUAUCUUUAUACAGAUUUUCUAGAAAUGUUUAGGUUACUAAAACAGGGUGGGCAAACUCUCUAAACUGGUACAAUUUUAUAGGUGAAAGAAAAAAUUCCCUCAUUUAAACCCAAUCAGAUGCCUCAGAGGGUAGCCUUGAUUUGUUCUUACAGUUAAGAAGCCCUGCAGAGCACAAACUUCAGAAACCCGGCUUCCUGUGCUAAGUCUUUCCCAAUCUCUACCCCUUUCUUCUCGGGCCACCCUCUGUUUAAAAUUUGUGCUGGGUUAUUCAGAACCUAAAAGUAUUAUUCAAACCAAUUUCUUCCUUCCACAGUUAUCUUAGCUGGAUAUAAUGUAUUUUCAGCUCAAUUGUUAAUGUGAUGGAUGGCACAAUGAAUGUAUAUUUUGUGUUAUUCGUGAAUAGUCUUUUGCAUGUCGCACAAUGUUUGAUGUCCCCAAAGUACCACACUGAGUUCUAUCAGUUAUCCUUUGUGAGCCUAUGAUAUUCCCCAUUUCCUGUACAAUCAUGAACAGCUCUGAGAUCCUGGAGUGAUAUGAUCCAGAGCAGAGUUUACGGGUCUUAGGAUGUCUGUAAUAAAUAAAUAUACUCAAGUUUCAGGUAUGCUUAAGCAUCCGUGUAUUUGGCUGGGCUACAAUUUGUUAAUUCCUAUGAAGUUGGCACAUUUCAUGAGGGGAAAGGGAGAAGGGUGGUAAAUAUUUUCAAAGAGAUGGGCCUUUUCUUGAAUAAAAGUUAAUAACAGCUCCUUUAUUAUAAUCAAAGCUCAUAAUGGAAAAAAAGACUGAUGAAGAAAUUUAUGAAGCAGAUUUAUUUUUGAAACAAACAUGGAUACUUCCUGGGUCAAGUGCUAACCUUUUCACCUCCAACUGGAUGUUGACGUAUAUAUAAACAGAACUCCCUUCAAAAGCCAAAA